AUUUGUGAAUACUUCUUGCUGGAAGUCCCUCACCCAGAGACCAGUGCUCCCAACGGCAGAGCAGCGGGGGAGGUAAGUGCUCAGACAUUAAGCCGUUGAGUAGAGGCAUGUUUUGCAAUCUCUCGUUUAGCUACCAAUUGGAGCAGUUUAACGUGCUUGAGUCCCCGGCGUGAUGUGUUCAUGGACGAAGUUGCCGAUGGAUGUUGUCAGGUGUUGCACCUGGAGGGCCCAGAUGGAUCAAUGAGGCAUUUAAAGUGUAGAAUCUCACCCUGAACCCAGACUAUUCAGGUCCGUUUUUCUAGGAAAGUUAUUUCUUUUUCACUUUUAGAUUCAAGUGCUCAUUUUCUUCUUCAAAUUUAGAGCACUUCAGUAUGAACAAUAUUUCUUUUGUUAAAAAAUAUUUCUUGGAAACAACUUAUUGAAGUUUCCUCAGAGUGGCCAAAGCCGAUGAUAAUUUUAUUCCAGAUAAAGAACUGGUGACACGUGGCUGUACAUUCAGCACAGCUGUGGUGUCCCCAAGUGCCAUGACCCAGGAGCCAUUCAGAGAGGAGCUGGCCUAUGACCGGAUGCCCACGCUGGAGCGGGGCCGGCAAGACCCCGCCAGCUAUGCCCCAGACGCGAAGCCGAGCGACCUGCAGCUGUCGAAGAGACUGCCCCCCUGCUUCAGCCACAAGACGUGGGUCUUCUCUGUGCUGAUGGGGAGCUGCCUCCUGGUGACCUCGGGGUUUUCGCUGUACCUGGGGAACGUGUUCCCGGCUGAGAUGGAUUACUUGCGCUGUGCUGCAGGCUCUUGCAUCCCCUCGGCAAUUGUGAGCUUCACCGUCUCCAGGAGGAACGCCAAUGUGAUUCCCAACUUUCAGAUAUUGUUUGUUUCCACGUUUGCUGUGACCACUACGUGUUUAAUUUGGUUUGGAUGCAAACUAGUCCUGAACCCAUCAGCAAUAAACAUCAACUUCAACCUCAUCCUGCUGCUCCUGCUGGAGCUGCUCAUGGCGGCCACGGUGAUCAUCGCUGCACGGUCCAGCGAGGAGGACUGCAAGAAAAAGAAGGGCUCCAUGUCUGACAGCGCCAACAUUCUGGACGAAGUGCCAUUUCCUGCUCGGGUCCUGAAAUCUUACUCAGUCGUCGAGGUAAUCGCAGGCAUCUCUGCCGUCCUCGGGGGGAUCAUUGCCCUGAACGUGGAUGACUCAGUUUCAGGCCCACACCUCUCAGUGACGUUCUUUUGGAUCCUAGUGGCCUGCUUUCCAAGUGCCAUUGCCAGUCAUGUGGCAGCAGAGUGUCCCAGCAAGUGUCUGGUGGAGGUCCUGAUUGCCAUAAGCAGCCUCACGUCUCCGCUGCUGUUCACAGCCUCUGGAUAUCUGUCAUUCAGCAUCAUGAGAAUCGUGGAGAUGUUUAAGGAUUACCCGCCAGCCAUAAAACCAUCCUACGAUGUGCUGCUGCUGCUGCUGCUGCUAGUGCUCCUGCUGCAGGCCGGCCUCAACACGGGCACCGCCAUCCAGUGCGUGCGCUUCAAGGUCAGUGCAAGGCUGCAGGGUGCAUCCUGGGACACCCAGAACGGCCCGCAGGAGCGCCUGGCUGGGGAGGUGGCCAGGAGCCCCCUGAAGGAGUUCGACAAGGAGAAAGCCUGGAGAGCCGUCGUGGUGCAAAUGGCCCAGUGACCCCCAGACGCGGAAACCGGGUGGCAGCGCCCAGCCUGGCCCCAAGCAUGGAAACGCACAACCCCUAAUCGCCCUGAGCUACUGCUUCUAACACCUCUUUUCCCUUGUGUGAGGGCAAACCAGGCUGCAGGUGGGGUUUUCACUUCCUAGGGUAGUUUAAUUUUAAAAUAGGCCAAUGUUGGCUAGUCUGUGCCUCAGUGAGAUCAGUCAGCUCCGAGUGGCUCCCGUGUCGUAACAGCAGGAGCAUGGCCGCAACUUCCCAGGCCGAGGAAGGGCCCCCGGCUCGGCCUCUUGAGAGCCCCACCCCUGAACUGGCCCCAGCUCCUCUUCCUGCCUCUCUCAUGGCUUGGGCUGGAGUGGGCUCUCUGGACCUGACCAGACUGUGGGUCCCUGCGUCUCCUGCCCACUCUGACCGGGCUUCCUCCCUCCACGCUUAGGGUCUGUCCCGGGUACUCAGUCAGCCCAGUGGGAUCUUACCCACUUCCCUGCAAGGUGCACCUGCCCCAGGCUCAGGCUGCCCAGCGGCUCUUCCUGGACAGUGAGAGCAGGGCUGGGCGCCUCUGUCCUGGCCCGGGAGCCGCAGGGGCCCCUCCUCCAGAGCCUGGGCGCAAGCGACACAGGCUGCCGCUGCUCUCCCAGGUGAAAUCCACACCAGUCCACGCCGGGUCGCCUGCCCUGUCUCCCUACUUAGACCCAGUCAUUCUAGAGGGAUCCACCGCCACACUGGCCGGCCCACGUCCUGGGUGCUGUCAUGCCCAGCUUGGAGUGCCACGUGGCCGCUGCCCACGUCCCGGGCACUGUCAUGCCCAGCUUGGAGUGCCACAUGGCCGCUGCCCACGUCCCGGGCACUGUCAUGCCCAGCUUGGAGUGCCACGUGGCCGCUGCUGUGACAGGCAGUGUUCUUGGGGGUGGGGCUGCAUCCAAGGCUUUGUAAACCGGCUGGACCACGUCUCCCUGGCCCCAGUGACCGGGGGAAGCUGAGCCCCUCCCUCCUGUGUUUGCUCCCAUUACUCAAAAUGCAGGACAGAUCAGGUCAGAGCCCAGGAAUUCUCACAGGUUCACCCAGCGCCCUCUACCUCCUAGCAAGUACUUUGUCUUGAUCCUCACUGAGAAGGCCCCAGGGCAGCGGUCUUCUCCAUCUCCGCUGUUUUGGGGUCUUAGGGUACAGCCCAGGCGGUCACUGCCCACCUGCCAGGCUGCAGGGACAGUUGGGUGUGAGAAUAACACUGGCUUUGGGUAGUGCCAUGGCCAGGAGUGGGUUUCCCUGCGUCUCCUCGUCCCGAGGGCGCCUGGGUCCUCCCAGCUGACGGCAGUAAAUCCACAGUGAGUUGGGGCGACUGUGAAACUGGAAUGCUGUUACUUUGAUAAUUACUUUCCAGCAGGUGUUUUCCUUCACAAUGGUUUUGUUUCUUUCCUUCUGAUCUGAGAAGACAUGAACGUUUUCUCUUCACCGCCGUGGGGUGUAUUGACUGGUCCCCCAUGGGCUGCUGGAAAGGCCCGGAGAUGCAUCUGUGGCCUGGGGCCAUCAAGAUCAAAGAACCAGGAGGCCUGGGAGAUGCAGCUGGAUGGGGCGGCCUGCAGACCCUGCCAGGGGGUUUGAGGACCCUCCCAGGUUUCCCACUGCGGAACAGGAGUGACUCUGGCUGCCAAGAUACCUUCAUGGUGUUCAUGACAAGUGGAAUCAUUAUUUUCAACCAUUGAAGGGGGAUGCAGGCAAGACACCUUCCCAGCUGCUCCUAGAGGGGACAAGCCAGGCCCUCUCUGCAGUCCUCGGCAGCUCCGGAAGGACACAGUCAGGGGCCGGGCAAACACUUUGGCCACAGCCCCAAACAAGCGCCACCGUGGGAGAGGAGAGGCUGCUGUCACUGGUACCGGAUGCAGACCCCACCCUGUCUGCAGGCCACCCCCACCUCCCUGCAGCUUUGAGGCUGGCGGGGUCUGCUCCUGGGAAUGGGGUGGGAGCCACAGGGACGACCCGGGGCGGGCUGAUGUCUUCUUGGGGGCAGACCAGAGAGCUCAAGUUUCAGAGUCAGAAUUAGGCACUUGGAGCGUUUUUGCUGGCUUGCACUUUCUUAUUUUCUUAUUUUAGAGCGCUUAAAAAAUCCGGAAAAAUGGGGUUUAAAAGAACUGUCUCUUUCAGUCUACAUUUUUGUUUAAUACGCUUGAGCAAUAAACGCUGACUUGCAGACGUG